ACACCUAUGCUACUGUAUGGUAUAGCCUAUAGCUCCCGGGCUAAAAUCCCGCACAGCAUGUCACUGUACUGAACGCUGUAGGCUGGGAACUGUAACAGGUGGUAAGUAUUUGUAUAUCUAAACAUAUCUAAAUGUAGAAAAGGGACACUAAAAAUACAGUAUCAUAAGUUUAUGGGACCACUGUCAUUAUGUGGCGAUGACUGCAUUUCUGAUCGUCAGCAAAGACGCAUUUAAGCCAUUCCUAUCAUCAUGUAUUUUGAUGCUCUGAUCUUCCUGGAUUUGGCCUUUGGGAGCUCCUGUGUCCUUCUGUCUCUCUUUCAUUCUCUGACCCCCUUGUUAGUUUCUGCGUGUCUCUGUCUCAUCUCUCUCAUUCUCUCUGUCUGCCUUUAUCUUGGUCUUUCUUUCUUCUCUGUCUGUCUGUUGCUCCUCUCUCUCUGUCCUGUCUGCUUCCCGCACCCCUCUCUCUCCCCUGUCCUUUUCUCUUUCUCUCUGUCCCCCUCUCUUUCUAUGCCUUUGCCUCUUUGCCUCUCUGGCUUUCUGCCUCUGACUCGGUCUCAUUUUGUCUGUUUUUCUCUCUGUCUUUCUAUGGCUUAGUCUCUGUCACUCAGGACUCACCUCUGCAGUGUCUUCAGAUAGGAGUCCUAGACACGCUGGCUUGUGUGUGGGAUACCAUCACUCUCCCUCCUCUGGACUCACAGUCCUCCUCUCCAGCCUCUAUUUCAGACCCAGGGGGCUCUGGAGCAGGUGCAAGGAGGGGAACAGGAAUGAGUGGAUUUUCCUCCCACCUGCUCUGCACACUGCAAGGCUGGGAUCAUGUCUCUGUGUGUGCGCCCACGUGUGUGGAGGGGUGUCAGAGAGGUCUGUGCCUGGGAGAGGGGAGAGAGGGAGCUGCUGGUGUCUGUGUCUUGCCCCCUCCUGCUACAGCUGGGAAGGGAAUCAGGUUAGACCCCAGGGUGAGUGCCUGGGGCAGGGGAUGCUUUCUGUGGGGAGUCCUCUGAAUAGGCCCCCCUGCCCCGCAGUGGGGCCCAAAAGGUGGGCAGUGUCUGUGCAGGGCUUUGCAUCUUAGAGCAUGUUCCCAUAUGUGAUUUCAAAGGACAGACUAUCAGAGCUCCAGGGGUGUGGUGCCAUCCAGAGAGAGAAACUGAGGCCUGUGGUAGUGGUGGAGUGGUGACUGACCCAGGGCUUUAUGGUAAGUCAGGCUCAGAGGAAGGCUUGGGCCACCAGCCUGCCUCUCAUGCAUGAGGUGGUGUCAUUUAGAAAAGGAUAGUCACAUCUCUGUGUUUUCAUAAUGCAAAGAAUUGAAAAUAAAAAUAAAGAUGGAAGAAGCCUUCCGGGCUGGGGCAGGGGAUGGUGGAGAGGGUGGAAUGGGGAGAGAAUGAGGGGAAAUGGCACUGUGGGGCCAUGGGUUAGAGAAGCGAAGGCCCAUCAGCAGUACAGUGGACAAAUAAACCUGCUGCAUCUACACAAUGGGACGGCGCACGGCAGAGACAAAGGAGAAGCUGUGUUGGAUGCAGCCACCCAAAGGGACCUCAGAUUCAUGCCAGAGGAUCUGGAGGCCCCCAAGACACACCGCUUCAAGGUGAAGACCUUCAAGAAGGUGAAGCCCUGUGGGAUCUGCCGCCAGGUCAUCACCCAGGAAGGCUGCACCUGCAAAGUCUGCAGCUUCUCCUGUCAUCGGAAAUGCCAGGCCAAGGUGGCUGCCCCCUGCGUUCCUCCAUCCAACCAUGAGCUGGUGCCCAUCACCACUGAGAAUGCACCAAAGAAUGUAGUGGACAAGGGAGAAGGAGCCUCCCGGGGUGGAAACACACGGAAAAGCCUCGAGGACAACGGCUCCACCAGGGUCACCCCGAGUGUCCAGCCCCACCUCCAGCCCAUCAGAAACAUGAGUGUGAGCCGGACCAUGGAGGACAGCUGUGAGCUGGACCUGGUGUACGUCACAGAGAGGAUCAUCGCUGUCUCCUUCCCCAGCACAGCCAAUGAGGAGAACUUCCGGAGCAACCUCCGUGAGGUGGCGCAGAUGCUCAAGUCCAAACAUGGAGGCAACUACCUGCUGUUCAACCUCUCUGAGCGGAGACCUGACAUCACGAAGCUCCAUGCCAAGGUACUGGAAUUUGGCUGGCCCGACCUCCACACCCCAGCCCUGGAGAAGAUCUGCAGCAUCUGUAAGGCCAUGGACACAUGGCUCAAUGCAGACCCUCACAAUGUCGUUGUUCUACACAACAAGGGAAACCGAGGCAGGAUAGGAGUUGUCAUCGCGGCUUACAUGCACUACAGCAACAUUUCUGCCAGUGCGGACCAGGCUCUGGACCGGUUUGCAAUGAAGCGGUUCUAUGAGGAUAAGAUUGUGCCCAUUGGCCAGCCAUCCCAAAGAAGGUACGUGCAUUACUUCAGUGGCCUGCUCUCCGGCUCCAUCAAAAUGAACAACAAGCCCUUGUUUCUGCACCACGUGAUCAUGCACGGCAUCCCCAACUUUGAGUCUAAAGGAGGAUGUCGGCCAUUUCUCCGCAUCUACCAGGCCAUGCAACCUGUGUACACAUCUGGCAUCUACAACAUCCCAGGAGACAGCCAGACUAGCGUCUGCAUCACCAUCGAGCCAGGACUGCUCUUGAAGGGAGACAUCUUGCUGAAGUGCUACCACAAGAAGUUCCGAAGCCCAGCCCGAGACGUCAUCUUCCGUGUGCAGUUCCACACCUGUGCCAUCCAUGACCUGGGGGUUGUCUUUGGGAAGGAGGACCUUGAUGAUGCUUUCAAAGAUGAUCGAUUUCCAGAGUAUGGCAAAGUGGAGUUUGUAUUUUCUUAUGGGCCAGAGAAAAUUCAAGGCAUGGAGCACCUGGAGAACGGGCCGAGCGUGUCUGUGGACUAUAACACCUCCGACCCCCUCAUCCGCUGGGACUCCUACGACAACUUCAGUGGGCAUCGAGAUGACGGCAUGGAGGAGGUGGUGGGACACACGCAGGGGCCACUAGAUGGGAGCCUGUAUGCUAAGGUGAAGAAGAAAGACUCCCUGCACGGCAGCACCGGGGCUGUUAAUGCCACACGUCCUACACUGUCGGCCACCCCCAACCACGUGGAACACACGCUUUCUGUGAGCAGCGACUCGGGCAACUCCACAGCCUCCACCAAGACCGACAAGACCGACGAGCCUGUCCCCGGGGCCUCCAGUGCCACUGCUGCCUUGAGUCCCCAGGAGAAGCGGGAGCUGGACCGCCUGCUGAGUGGCUUUGGCUUAGAGCGAGAGAAGCAAGGCGCCAUGUACCACACCCAGCACCUCAGGUCCCGCCCAGCAGGGGGCUCGGCUGUGCCCUCCUCUGGACGCCACGUUGUCCCAGCCCAGGUUCAUGUCAAUGGUGGGGCGUUAGCAUCUGAGCGGGAGACAGACAUCCUGGACGAUGAAUUGCCAAACCAGGAUGGUCACAGUGCGGGCAGCAUGGGCACACUCUCUUCUCUGGACGGGGUCACCAACACCAGUGAGGGGGGCUACCCAGAGGCCCUGUCCCCACUGACCAACGGUCUGGACAAGUCCUACCCCAUGGAGCCUAUGGUCAAUGGAGGAGGCUACCCCUACGAGUCUGCCAGCCGGGCGGGGCCUGCCCAUGCUGGCCACACGGCCCCCAUGCGGCCCUCCUACUCUGCACAGGAGGGUUUAGCUGGCUACCAGAGGGAGGGGCCCCACCCAGCCUGGCCACAGCCAGUGACCACCUCCCACUAUGCCCAUGACCCCAGCGGUAUGUUCCGCUCUCAAUCCUUUUCGGAAGCUGAACCCCAGCUGCCCCCAGCUCCGGUCCGAGGGGGAAGCAGCCGGGAGGCUGUGCAAAGGGGACUGAAUUCGUGGCAGCAGCAGCAGCAGCAGCAGCAGCAGCCUCGCCCACCUCCACGCCAGCAGGAAAGAGCCCACUUGGAGAGUCUUGUAGCCAGCAGGCCCAGCCCUCAGCCAUUGGCAGAGACCCCCAUCCCCAGUCUCCCUGAGUUCCCGCGAGCAGCCUCCCAGCAGGAGAUUGAACAGUCCAUCGAAACACUCAAUAUGCUGAUGCUGGACCUGGAGCCAGCCUCCGCUGCUGCCCCACUACACAAGUCCCAGAGUGUCCCCGGGGCCUGGCCAGGGGCUUCUCCACUCUCCUCCCAGCCCCUCUCUGGAUCCUCCCGUCAGUCCCAUCCACUGACCCAGUCCAGAUCUGGCUAUAUCCCCAGUGGGCAUUCGUUGGGAACCCCUGAGCCAGCCCCACGGGCCUCUCUGGAGUCUGUCCCUCCUGGCAGGUCUUACUCACCUUAUGACUAUCAGCCAUGUUUGGCUGGGCCUAACCAGGAUUUCCAUUCAAAGAGCCCAGCCUCUUCCUCCUUGCCUGCCUUCCUUCCGACCACCCACAGCCCUCCAGGGCCUCAGCAACCCCCAGCCUCUCUCCCUGGCCUCACUGCUCAGCCUCUGCUCUCACCAAAGGAAGCGACUUCAGACCCCUCCCGGACUCCAGAGGAGGAGCCAUUGAAUUUAGAAGGGCUGGUGGCCCACAGGGUAGCAGCGUACAACGCCAGGCUGCAGGGCAUCGGACACAGUGGCAGCUUCCCGCCCCCUCCUCUCCACCGGCUCCAAUCUUCCUCCCUCUCUGGGGUACAGGCUCGGGAGAAGCAGCCUGCAGAGCCCCCAGCCCCUCUGCGGAGGCGGGCGGCCAGUGAUGGACAGUAUGAGAACCAGUCUCCAGAAGCCACAUCCCCUCGUAGCCCUGGGGUUCGCUCCCCUGUCCAGUGUGUCUCCCCGGAGCUGGCUCUUACCAUCGCUCUCAAUCCUGGAGGGCGGCCCAAAGAGCCCCAUUUGCACAGCUACAAGGAGGCCUUCGAGGAGAUGGAGGGAACCUCCCCGAGCAGCCCACCACCCAGUGGGGUGCGGUCCCCCCCGGGUCUGGCCAAGACACCCCUGUCUGCUCUGGGCCUGAAACCUCACAACCCAGCGGACAUCCUGUUGCACCCCACAGGAGUUACCAGAAGACGGAUCCAGCCAGAUUCUCUUUCUCAAGAAAUAAUCCCUGUUAAUCUCUUUCUCUCUUUUUCCUUUUUUGCUCUUCCUCAUCUUCACCACCUGCCCUUCUUUCCUGCCUCUCCUUCCUCCCACCUCUCUUCUCGUCUUCCCUCAGAGGAAGAUGAGGGGAAGGUGGUGGUCAGGCUGUCAGAAGAGCCCCGGAGCUAUGUGGAGUCUGUGGCACGGACAGCGGUGGCUGGACCCCGAGCUCAGGACUCUGAGCCCAAGAGCUUUAGUGCUCCAGCCACCCAGGCCUAUGGCCAUGAGAUACCCCUGAGGAACGGGACCCUGGGUGGCUCCUUUGUCUCCCCCAGCCCCCUCUCCACCAGCAGCCCCAUCCUCAGUGCUGACAGCACUUCAGUGGGGAGUUUCCCGUCGGGAGAGAGCAGUGACCAGGGUCCCCGGACGCCCACCCAGCCUCUGUUGGAGUCUGGCUUCCGCUCAGGCAGCCUGGGACAGCCCAGCCCGUCUGCCCAGAGAAACUACCAGAGCUCUUCUCCUCUCCCGACUGUGGGCAGUAGCUACAGCAGCCCCGACUACUCACUUCAGCAUUUCAGCUCCUCUCCGGAAAGCCAGGCUCGAGCUCAGUUCAGUGUGGCUGGCGUCCACACGGUGCCUGGGAGCCCUCAGGCGCGCCACAGAACAGUGGGCACCAACACUCCCCCUAGUCCUGGCUUCGGCUGGCGGGCCAUCAAUCCCAGCAUGGCUGCCCCCAGCAGUCCCAGUUUGAGCCAUCACCAGAUGAUGGGUCCACCAGGCACUGGCUUCCAUGGUAGCACUGUCUCCAGCCCCCAGAGCAGUGCAGCGACCACCCCGGGGAGCCCCAGCCUGUGUCGGCACCCAGCAGGGGUCUACCAGGUUUCUGGCCUCCACAACAAAGUGGCCACCACCCCGGGGAGUCCCAGCCUGGGCCGGCACCCUGGGGCUCACCAAGGCAACCUGGCCUCCGGUCUUCAUAGCAAUGCAAUAGCCAGCCCUGGAAGCCCCAGCCUGGGCCGUCACCUCGGAGGGUCUGGAUCUGUGGUUCCCGGCAGCCCCUGCUUGGACCGGCAUGUGGCCUAUGGUGGCUAUUCUACCCCGGAGGAUCGGAGACCCACACUGUCCCGGCAGAGCAGUGCCUCUGGCUACCAGGCUCCUUCCACGCCCUCCUUCCCUGUCUCCCCUGCCUACUACCCUGGCCUGAGCAGCCCUGCCACCUCCCCGUCACCAGACUCCGCAGCCUUCCGGCAAGGGAGCCCAACACCAGCCUUGCCAGAGAAGCGAAGGAUGUCAGUGGGAGACCGGGCAGGCAGCCUCCCCAACUAUGCCACCAUCAAUGGGAAGGUGUCUUCGCCUGUCGCCAGCGGCAUGUCCAGUCCCAGUGGGGGCAGCACCGUCUCCUUCUCCCACACUCUGCCCGACUUCUCCAAGUACUCCAUGCCAGACAACAGCCCGGAGACGCGGGCUAAAGUGAAGUUUGUCCAGGACACUUCUAAGUAUUGGUACAAGCCUGAGAUCUCCAGGGAGCAGGCCAUCGCGCUCCUCAAGGACCAGGAGCCGGGGGCCUUCAUCAUCCGCGACAGUCACUCCUUCCGAGGCGCGUACGGGCUGGCCAUGAAGGUGUCUUCGCCACCUCCAACCAUCAUGCAGCAGAAUAAAAAAGGAGACAUGACCCAUGAGCUGGUCAGGCAUUUUCUGAUAGAGACUGGCCCCAGAGGAGUCAAGCUCAAGGGCUGCCCCAAUGAGCCAAACUUCGGAUCGCUGUCUGCCCUGGUCUACCAGCACUCCAUCAUCCCAUUGGCCCUGCCUUGCAAGCUGGUCAUUCCAAACCGAGACCCCACAGAUGAAUCGAAAGAUAGCUCCGGCCCUGCCAACUCAACUGCAGACCUGCUGAAACAAGGGGCAGCCUGCAAUGUGCUCUUCGUCAACUCUGUGGACAUGGAGUCACUCACUGGGCCACAGGCCAUCUCUAAAGCCACAUCUGAGACGUUGGCUGCAGACCCCACGCCAGCUGCCACCAUCGUUCACUUCAAAGUCUCUGCCCAGGGAAUCACUCUGACUGACAACCAGAGAAAGCUCUUUUUCAGACGCCACUACCCUCUCAACACUGUCACCUUCUGUGACCUGGAUCCACAGGAAAGAAAGUGGAUGAAAACAGAGGGUGGUGCCCCUGCUAAGCUCUUCGGCUUCGUGGCCCGGAAGCAGGGCAGCACCACGGACAACGCCUGCCACCUCUUUGCUGAGCUUGACCCCAACCAGCCGGCCUCUGCCAUCGUCAACUUCGUCUCCAAGGUCAUGCUGAAUGCCGGCCAAAAGAGAUGAACCCUGCCCCUUGCCCAGGGCCAGUGCCAUGGGGAAGGGGCUUGUGGGGAGGGGACCCAUGAAUCCUGACCACUCUUGAACCCAGAAGGAGGACUUUGGGCCAAUUUCGGAGGAGAGAAGAAAGUGCAACGUGGGGAGAGGGAAGUGAAUUGCAGAGGGGAGGGGGAAAAGAGAGAGAGAGAGAGAGAGAGAGAGAGAGAGAAAGAUGGAGGAGAAGAACUUGGAUUCCCCUGGGUAGAUGGAAACUGCAAAAACCCAAAGCCUCCAAAACUAACCAGGUCCACCUAACACCCCCUCCCUCCCCUAAGAAGAUGGAUGUCCUCAAAAGAGAAGGAACAAACCUCCUUGGGAAUCCACAUUUUUUGGGGGAAUGGAAAAGCUCUGUCUCCCUAACUCAACUGCUUUGCAAGGGGAAAUCAAGCUGGGAGAAUCUUUUUCUGGCCACCUGUGGGGUAGGUUGUCAAACCAAACAGAGCCACCGUGGGACAUCAAGUGGAAGAACUUGUUUGCUUGAAAGUAUCUCAGACCCAAGGCACCUCAGGUCUCUUUGCUGUGCCUCCACUAUAUUGUCGUGUGGGUGUGUGUCUGCACCCACAUCCUCACACAUUGAUCUAGAUCUGCCUUUAUCCACUCGAAUUAUAAACAGCUCGGCUUGUCCUUGUCCCAUGUGUUUGUAGACACACAUGCAUACUGUCCAAAGAUUAGGGUUGGUGGUGGCAGUGCAGCAGGGGAGGGACAAACAACCAAGCUAUGGGUGACAGAGGCUCUCUCCUGGUGCCUGCACCUGCACUCUAGUGACCCUGGGUGCCGCCAGACCCUUCUCUUCUACAAAGACCCCAGCAGGAGUGGGAGGGUCUGCAAUGGCAUCGCCCUGUCCUGCCUUGGCCAGAAGCCUGGAGCUUUGGUUUGAGGAGGUAGAGAUAUGUGUAUCCAUAGGAAGAGAUCUGUCAGAACAGGCAGCUGUUGAGCUCGGGGUGUCUUCCCCAAGGCAUGUGGCUCAGCAGCAAGAAAGGCAAGUUGCUCCUGCUGGGGCCCUGGACUCUGCCUUAGCUCCCACCUCUCAGCCUUGUUAUUGGGUUUCAUGCCCCUGGACCAGCCUUAUCUCAGACCUGCUUACCUGCAUGAUGCCUUUUUGGGGGCUGGGGAUUGAGUCUUGCUGCUCUGCCCAGCCCUGUUCUAUUCUGCAGGGUCCCUGUGUUGGAAUUCUCCCUGGGGAACCUACUUUCUGCUCAGUGAGGCUCCGGCCAGAAACCUGGAGUCCUUAUCCUCCCCUCUGUAAGUGUUUUAGGGUCUGGCUUUUGCAGGCACCCUCUGACCUCAGCAGAGCUCCUGGGCCUGCUGCCUGCACACCACAUCGCCUACCUACAAUGCCAAAGCCUCACUGUCACCCUUUCUGCCUUGGUUUCCCUAGCUGAGCCACGCUGCCCAUGCAGCAGAGGGCAGAAGGCUUGCACUUGGGCCAAAGGGCCUAAGGUCCACUGGACAGUUGGGAAAACACCUGACCACCAUUUAAGGACUCUAAGCCAGAAUGGAAAAUUCACCAGGACUCCAUUCUUAAGCCUAUGCGAGUCCCCUAGAGAGAGGCAUUGUACUGAUAUAUAAAUAUUAUAUAAUAUAUACAUGAGACAUACUGACAGAAUCUGUAAGCUAAUAAAAUGUAAGAAAAGGUUAAAAAAAGAAUAGGUAAAUUGACAAGAAGUAUUUAUUGUUUUUCCAUAUUGCUUUAUUGCCUUCCUUGGGGAUAAACCAAUUCCUAUCCUUUUUUAUAUGUGUAAGUAAAGCCUGAAGUGUAGGGGGCCUUUGUUCUUGAAGCAGCCAGGGUCUCCUUGCCCUGGCCUUGGCCUUCCCUAGACUGUGUGGGGCUCAGCAUUGGGAGGGGUUGCACAUGUCCCAGCCUUUGGCCCCCUUACUUUUCAGCAAGCCAGGGGCCCAGCAGUCAGCUCCCAGGAUGUGUGGGGAGCUGUCCCUGACUCUGCAGGCCUGAGCGAGUGUGUGAGCAUGCGGGGACAUGGGUGUGUAUGGCACACAUAGGUGCGUGUGUGUCUUUUGUAUUUUUUCUCCUCCAAGGAGCUGUGUCAGUGUGGACGUUCUGUUUCAGGGAGUUGGAAAGGAGGGUGUCUGCAGAAGGUGGAGAGCAGGGGCAGAGGCCCCACUGGCCACCCCCUGCUUCCCAGAGUGAAACCUUGUGCCUGGUGACCAAAGUCCCUCCAAAGUGCUCUUCCUUCUGGGUUAUUCAAGCCAAAUAUCUGGGUUUCCCCCUCUCCUCAUUCCCUAGCAAACCCCAAUUAUCUUCCAAGAUAGGAGAUAUUUCCCAUCCCCUUCCUUUGUAAAUAUCUCAUCUCCCACUGGAGAGCCCAGGAGCCUAUUCCUGGCAUGGAUGUUCUGUCCACACUUGAGGCUGGGCGGUGUAUCAGACCCUUCAAGCAGCCUGGCUGGGGCCCAGGACUGAGUCUGGGGUCAGCUUUCACGGUCGCUUUUCCCUUCCUCACCACCCACCACAGCCCACCUUGCAUGCAUGGCCAGCCCCUCCACUCCAGCCUGAGCCAUGUGUGCCCCUGCGGGAGGACCCAUUCAUGCCAGAAAGCUGGUAACUCCCUCCCAGCAUCCCUGCGGAAGGAGUCAGUUUCUGAGAGUGUGACUUUUCAAGGCGAAUGAUGGGGAAGGGUUCCCCAGUCCCCACAGUGGCCCCACCUCUGGGCCCUGCACCAGAGCCCUUCUGUGUCACGGCGGGCUGUGCACCCAUGCACACACCUACGCACACACAACACUCCGCACUGCAGUAUAUUCUUGCCAAAGAUUUCCUUUAAAAGCAAGCACUUUUACUAAUUAUUAUUUUGUAAAUGUUUAUCUUCUUCUGUCUUCUCCCUCCCUGAAUCUAUUUUACUGUUGUUUAUUGUUGAAUCUGUGUGUCAGCCAGGAGAGCGCUGUCUGGCCUUGAACAUGGGCUGGGAUGGGAAAGGGUCUGGGAGAAGAUGGGCAACAAAGAGCCAGGGAGUCAUGGACAUCGCAGCGACGCAGACCCCAGCAGGUUCAGUCCCGUGCUGCCACCAGCUGUCCAGCUGGGUGUCUGGAGGGAAGAGGGCAGAGGAGGGUCAUGUCCCUUCAGCUGGGGGAGGGGCCCAGUGAGCUCCACGUGGCUUUUUCCCAAAGGGAGCAAGAGGGAAGGAUUGGGCGAGAAAACAAUGGAGAGGGGACCUGCGAAGGAAAACAGGGAGGAAGUGAGCGGUUUGAUCAGCCUGCUAUCACGGUGUUCUGGCUCUCUUAUUUAGCCAGGCGCUUAAGGGACAGAUACAUCACAUCCUAAGUUUGGGAAAGGCCUUUGACCCAUGUCAUCUGAGCGUCUCCUCCAGUAGCUCUGAAAGCUGUGGACACCAAUGGCCAGGAUUCCUUCUCCCCUGGUUUUUGAGGAUCCCUGGGUCUUCUGAGACUGGCCAGGAGAGGGAUGGUGGGGCCAGUGGUUGUGUGAAAGCAGGAGGGGCAGCCCUCCUGGACAAGUGUGAUCCCCCUAUAAACGGCUCUCAGGAGGUUAGUGAGUAGGAGAUUCUGCCUUGUUCUGAUGAGCCUGUGCAGGGGCUCCAGGGGAGCAUGCUGUCCAGGGGGCACAGAAGGGUGGUGAGUGUGAUCAAAUCUAGUCUCACUCCCACUUUUUAGUCUCACUCCUACUUUUGUCCACCACCCCUGCCUCCUGGAUCUUCUCCCACUUUUUUUUUCAGCUUUAGGACCUGGGGAGAUCCUGUGAGUCAAGGCAGACACCCAAUCCUGCCCCCACACUCGGGGUCCUCCAAGAGGUUGGGGGGCAGAGUCCCAGAGCAGCCCUUUACCCCAGGUCCAGGCCCUGGAAUCCUGAGACUCGCGUUUCCUUGGCCAGUGGUAACACAGGACGUGUGUGCGCAUGUGCAAGUGUGGAUGUAUGUGUGUGCGUGUGUUUUGCUCAUUUCUUUAGGGAACUUGGGAGUCGGGGUUGGAGGUGCUGGGCAAUGGAACUUCAAAUUCAAUGUCGCCCAGCAGUGAGGGGAGUCGGGAGGUGAGGCCUGUAGGCCAACCAAUUGGUGGAGUCUCAGCGAUAGCCCAGGUGAGAAGUGGUUCACCCAGAGGGGCAGGGUGGGGGCCUCGGGCAGAUCUGUCCCUCUUGGCACCUCUGUCCUCAAAUGUCCAAAAUGUUGGAGGACCUCUGUUCAUAUCCCACGCCUGGGCUCUUGCCAGCAGUGGAGUUACUGUAGAGGGAUGUCCCAAGCUUGUUUUCCAAUCAGUGUUAAGCUGUUUGAAACUCUCCUGUGUCUGUGUUUUGUUUGUGCGUGUGUGUGAGAGCACAUCAGUGUGUGCAGGCUGUGUUUCCCCAUUUCUCUCCUCCCUUCAGACCCAUCAUUGAGAACAAAUGUAAGAAAUCCCUUCCCACCACCCUCCCUGCCUCCCAGGCCCUCUGCGGGGGAAACAAGAUCACCCAGCAUCCUUCCCCACCCCAGCUGUGUAUUUAUAUAGAUGGAAAUAUACUUUAUAUUUUGUAUCAUCGUGCCUAUAGCCGCUGCCACCGUGUAUAAAUCCUGGUGUAUGCUCCUUAUCCUGGACAUGAAUGUAUUGUACACUGACGCGUCCCCACUCCUGUACAGCUGCUUUGUUUCUUUGCAAUGCAUUGUAUGGCUUUAUAAAUGAUAAAGUUAAAGAAAACUC